CUCUUUCCUCCUCCUCCCGCAGCUCCAUUCAUUGGUCCCGCCGCACCGGGCCUGCUGGGCUCCGCUUCCGUUCCACUGCUCAGCUGCCGCCUGGUGGGGCCACCAAGGGCAGGCAUCCCAGGGGCUUUGUCUGACUGGACUGGGCCAGUGCAGAAUGGGGGUUCAGGCAGGGCUGUUUGGGAUGCUGGGCUUCCUGGGGGUGGCCCUGGGGGGCUCCCCUGCCCUCCGCUGGUACAGGACCUCCUGCCACUUGACCAAGGCCGUCCCUGGCAACCCACUGGGGUACCUGAGCUUCCUGGCCAAGGAUGCUCAGGGACUGGCCCUGAUCCAUGCCCGCUGGGAUGCGCAUAGGAGGCUGCAGUCAUGUAGCUGGGAGGAUGAGCCGGAGCUCACCGCAGCCUACGGUGCUCUCUGUGCUCAUGAGACUGCCUGGGGCUCCUUCAUCCACACCCCCGGACCCGAGCUGCAGAGAGCACUGGCCACUCUUCAGAGUCAGUGGGAGGCAUGCCGAGCGCUUGAGGAGAGUCCAGCAGGGGCCAGGAAGAAGCGAGCAGCAGGGCAGAGUGGAGUCCCUGGUGGAGGGCACCAGCGAGAGAAGAGAGGAUGGACCAUGCCUGGCACACUGUGGUGUGGAGUUGGAGAUUCUGCUGGGAACUCCUCGGAGCUGGCUUUGAAACUCUGAGAGUCCCACAGAAGGGAGAGUGACUGGUCUGAGGACCCUCAUGGCGUUUGUGUCAGGGCUGGGGUGAGAACCAGGGGUCUUCCAGGGACCUGAUCUCUGUUGCCGGGAACAUGACCGCUGCCCACAGAACAUCUCACCCUUGCAGUACAACUAUGGCAUCCGAAACUACCGAUUCCACACCAUCUCCCACUGUGACUGUGACACCAGGUUGGUGGCAGGCAGCGAGGGCCCAGAGCUCAGGGACAGGGCAGAGUUACCCAGUUCCUGGGUAACUAGACAUUGGGAUUGCAGAGGAUCUUAAAGCUCAGCCAGCUUGGACCCCACAGUGCAGGUAGGAAAGCUGAGGCCAGAAAGAAGGGAUGCUUGGACCCCAAACCACCCAGCUGGUAGUGGCACAGUGGGCUGUGGGAGGAGCCAGACAGCCCUCCAUGCCCCAGGGUCCUGGGUAUCUGUUCUGGGGCAGGUUUCAGCAAUGCCUACAGAAUCAGCACGACUCCAUCUCGGACAUCGUGGGCGUGGCCUUCUUCAACGUGCUGGAGAUCCCCUGCUUUGUGCUGGAGGAGCAGGAGGCGUGUGUGGCGUGGUACUGGUGGGGCGGGUGUAGGAUGUACGGCACAGUGCCCCUCGCUCGCCUGCAGCCCAGGACCUUCUACAAUGCCUCCUGGAGCUCCCGGGCCACCUCCCCAACUCCCAGCUCCCGGAGCCCAGCCCCUCCCAAGCCUCGACAGAAGCAGCACCUUCGGAAGGGGCCACCACAUCAGAAAGGGUCCAAGCGCCCCAGCAAAGCCAACACCACAGCCCUCCAGGACCCUAUGGUCUCUCCCAGGCUUGAUGUGGCCCCCACAGGCCUCCAGGGCCCACAGGGUGGCCUAAAACCUCAGGGUGCCCGCUGGGUCUGCCGCAGCUUCCGCCGCCACCUGGACCAGUGUGAGCACCAGAUUGGGCCCCGGGAAAUCGAGUUCCAGCUGCUCAACAGCGCCCAAGAGCCCCUCUUCCACUGCAACUGCACGCGCCGUCUGGCACGCUUCCUGAGGCUCCACAGCCCACCCGAGGUUACCAACAUGCUUUGGGAGCUGCUGGGCACAACCUGCUUCAAGCUGGCCCCUCCACUGGACUGUGUGGAAGGCAAAAACUGUUCCAGAGACCCUAGGGCCAUCAGGGUGUCAGCCCGGCACUUGCGGAGGCUUCAGCAGAGGCGACACCAGCUCCAGGAUAAAGGCACAGAUGAGAGGCAGCCAUGGCCUUCAGAGCCCCUGAGAGGCCCCAUGUCAUUCUACAACCAGUGCCUGCAGCUAACCCAGGCAGCCAGGAGACCCGACAGGCAGCAGAAGUCCUGGAGCCAGUGACCUCAGUUUCAGCUUUCCUGGGCACCAGCCUGGACCUUGCCCAUGGCUAUGCCAAGCCUUGGGAAUCUCAGCCUCCCCUCCGUAGGUUAGACUGAAGCAUGGCAGAGGCUGUUGUGGACAAUCAAGAGGAUGAAUGGGGGGAUCUCAAGGCCCAAAUGCUGGACCACAUCUCCUGCUGUUCUGGGUAACCUUGAGCUAUGUAUGACACAACUCUUCUAUGCCUGGAUGUGGUGUUCAGGAAGCUCAUUCUGAUGCCCUGGGCUUUGGCCUUGCCAGGGAACUUCACAUACAGAUGAGAAUGGGGAAAGGGUAACUUAUUGCAGCAGCCCCAGGCAGUACCAGGAGGAGGUACAUGUAUGUCCGUGUUGCAAAAAUAAUACAUGCCUCAAAAACCUGCCUAGGGGAGCCCUAGUGCCUGGGUGCUGUGGCCUGAGGUAGCAGGUGGGAAGUUAGGGAUGUCACAGAAAUGUCUGUGUCUGAAUCCAGGAUUGGGGUGGGUGUUGGAGAGGGCUUUCAGCUCCCCUCCUCCCAGGGGGGCCUCUUUUUUUAACGGCUGCCGUGCCCUUCCUGGCCCAGCCCUAAACCUAAAUUCAAAUCUCCUCCAUGCCUUUGCGCAAAGGACCUCCCUCUUGCACUCUAAGCCUUAGUUUCCUCCUCUAAAAAAAGGGGGUCUCUAAACAGGAGCUACCUCAUAGGGUUGUUGAGGAUUAAGUGAACCAAUACAUAUACAGUGCUUAGCACUUAAUAAGUAUUCCCCCCUGCGACACCUAGCUGAACUAUGGUUUGGUGUCUGAUCUUGAGAGGUUGAUGUAACCUUUUAAAGGCCUCAGUUCGCUCACCUGUGAAAUGGGUCUAAGAAUAGCACUGAUCUCACAGGGUUGUGAUGCAGAUUAAAGGAGAUGGCAUGUGUAAUGUA